AUGACCGGCUCCUGCUGCGGCUCCACCUUCUCCUCCCUGAGCUACGGGGGAGGCUGCUGCCAGCCCUGCUGCUGCCGCGACCCCUGCUGCUGCCGCCCCGUGACCUGCCAGACCACCGUGUGCCGCCCCGUGACCUGCGUGCCCCGCUGCACGCGCCCCAUCUGCGAGCCCUGCCGCCGCCCGGUGUGCUGCGACCCCUGCUCCCUGCAGGAAGGCUGCUGCCGCCCCAUCACCUGCUGCCCCUCGUCGUGCACGGCUGUGGUGUGCAGGCCCUGCUGCUGGGCCACCACCUGCUGCCAGCCUGUGUCUGUGCAGUCCCCCUGCUGCCGGCCCCCCUGCGGCCAGCCGACCCCUUGCAGCACCACCUGCAGGACCUCCUCCUGCUGAGCCACCACCUGCUGCCAGCCUGUGUCUGUGCAGUCCCCCUGCGGCCAGCCGACCCCUUGCAGCACCACCUGCAGGACCUCCUCCUGCUGAGCCACCACCUGCUGCCAGCCUGUGUCUGUGCAGUCCCCCUGCGGCCAGCCGACCCCUUGCAGCACCACCUGCAGGACCUCCUCCUGCUGAGCAGCCCGUUAUCACGAAGGGCCCCUCAGAAGAUGGCCAGGUCCAUCCCGCUGCCCCUCAGGGCUUCACCGCAGAGCAAUACACGUUUCCUUGAGAAGCCCAUUUCUCAUCUCUUCAUACUAGCUCACACUAUGCAUUGAAGACACCUUUUCAGACCAACCACAGAUGAGAAAUACUUUUCCUAGGACUCCAGUCUAACUCCUAUAUCAUGUUGUCUGCUUUCUAAUAAACUCAAUACUCCUACCAUAGAAA